ACUUCCUCUGACCCACCAUUCGGCAGGGAGACAUGAUGGAAGCGGAUCGCCCAGAGAAGCUUUUCAUUGGGGGCCUCAACCUCAAAACCGACGAGAAAGCCCUCAAAGCCGAGUUUGGCAAGUAUGGCCACAUCAUCAAGGUGUUCCUGAUGAAAGACCGAAAAACCAACAAGUCGAGGGGCUUCGCGUUCGUCACCUUCGAAAGCCCUGCAGACGCCAAGGCUGCCGCCAGAGAUAUGAACGGCAAGUACCUGGAUGGUAAGGCCAUCAUGGUGGCCCAGACCAUCAAACCGGCAUUCAAGAGCAGCCGAUGGGUCCCGCCAACCCCCGGCAGCGGCAGUCGCUCAAGGUUCUCACACAGAACCCGUGGGGGUGGCAGCAGCCCACAGCGACCCCCCUCUCAGGGCAGGCCUGAUGACGGCCGCGGCUACGCGGGGUAUUUCGACCUGUGGCCCUACAGGGCCCCGAUGCCCAGGAAGCGCGGGCCGCCACCGCGGCACUGGGCCAGCCCACCCCACAAGAGGGCCACGCCGUCGAGCCUGGCUCACAGCGUUGGCUGUGGAAUGCGCGGGAAGGCACCGACUGUGUCGGGGCAAGAUGGCUACUCAGGCUUGCAGCCACGGCGCUGGGCCGGCCCACCCCACAAGAGGGCUGUGCCCCGGUCAAGCCUGGCUCGCAUUGGCGGCAGUGGAAUGCCUGGGAAGGCCCCGGCCGUGUGGGGGCAAGAUGGCUACUCAGGCCCGCGGGUCCGGGAGCCACUGCCCCCGUGCCGCGACCCUGGGGAUUUUGUCCCUGCGCUCAGAGACUACAGCCGCCGCUAUUAUGGCCACUCCAGUGUCCCGGACUACCGUCCCUUGAGAGGCGACGGCAACCAAAAUGGCUACAGGGGUCGCGACCAUGAGUACACAGAUCAUCCCAGCAAAGGCUCCUACCGAGAGCCCCUCAAGAGCUACGGAGGCCCAUGCGGCGCUGCCCCUGUGUGGGGGACACCGCCAUCUUAUGGAGGAGGAUGCCGCUACGAGGAGUACCAGGGCAACUCGCCCGAUGCCUGCAGUGAAGGCCGCUCGUCCGAGGCCUUGCCAGUCGUCUUGCCAGACGCCUACAGCAGGGACCACUCGCCCAAAGCCUAUAGUGGGGGCCGCAGCAGUUCCAGUAACGGUUACAGCCGGAGUGACCGCUACGGAGAAGAAGGCUGCUACGAGGAGUACAGAGGCCGCUCGCCCGACGCCCACAGCGGGGGCCGCAACAGUUCCAGCAACAGUUACGGCCAGAGCCACCACUAUGGAGGAGAAGGCCGCUAUGAGGAGUACCGAGGCCGCUCACACGAGGCCCGCAGCGGGGGCCGCUCCACUGAUGCCCACAGCAGGGGCCGGUCCGACGACGCCUACAGUGGGGGCCAUGACAGUUCCAGCUGGAGCGACUGCUGCGGAGGAGGAGGCCGUUAUGAGGAGUACCAAGGCCGCUCGCUGGAUGCCAACAGUGGAGGCUGCUCGCCCGAGGCCUACAGUGGGGGCCACGACAAUUCCAGCUGGAGCGACCGCUACGGAGUAGGAGGCCACUAUGAGGAGAACCGAGGCCACUCUCUGGAUGCCAACAGCGGAGGCCGUUCACCCGACACCCACAGUGGGGGCCACAGCAGUUCCAGCAACAGUUACGGCCAGAGCCACCGCUAUGGAGGAGAAGGCCGCUAUGAGUACCGAGGCCGCUCGCAUGACGCCCACAGUGGGGGCUGCUCUGCCGACGCCUACAGUGGGGGCCACGACAGUUCCAGCCAGAGCAACCGCUACGGAGGAGGAGGCUGCUACGAGGAGUACCGAGGCCGCUCCCUCGAUGCCAACAGUGGAGGCCGCUCGCCCAAUGCCUACAGCGGGGGCCACGACAGUUCCAGCUGGAGCCACCGCUACGGAGGAGGAGGCCGCUACGAGGAGUACCGAGGCCGCUCCCUUGAUGCCAACAGUGGAGGCCGCUCGCCUGAUGCCUACAGUGGGGGCCACGACAGUUCUGGCCAGAGCAACUGCUACGGAGGAGGAGGCCGCUACGAGGAGUACCGAGGCCGCUUGCUCGAUGCCAACAGUGGAGGCCGCUCGCCUGAUGCCUACAGUGGGGGCCACGACAGUUCCAGCCAGAGCAACCGCUAUGGAGGAGGCGGCCGCUACGAGGAGUACCGAGGCCACUCGCUUGAUGCCAACAGCGGAGGCCGCUCGCCUGACACCUACAGCCGGGGCCACGACAGUUCCAGCCAGAGCGACCACUAUGGAGGAGGAGGUCGCUCACUCGAUGCCAACAGCAGUGGCCGCUUGCCUGACGCCUACAGUGGGGGCCAUGACAGUUCCAGCCGGAGCCACCGCUACGGAGGAGGAGGCCGCUACGAGGAGUACCGAGGCCGCUCGCUCGAUGCCAACAGCGGAGGCCGCUCACCCAAUGCCUACAGCGGGGGCCACAACAGUUCCAGCCGGAACGACCCCUGCAGAGGAGGAGGCCGCUACGAGGAGAACCGAGGUCACUCUCUCGAUGCCAACAGCGGAGGCCACUCACCCAACGCCUACAGUGGGGGCCGUGACAGUUCCAGCAACAGUUACGACCGGAGCCACCGCUAUGGAGGAGGAGGCCACUACGAAGAGUACCGAGGCCGCUCGCACGACACCCACAGCAGGGGCCGAUCGCCCGAUGCCCACAGCGGGGACCACUACACCGAAGCCUACAGCAGGGGCCGCGACAGUUUCAGCAACAGCUAUGGCCGGAGUGACCAUUACGGAAGAGGAGGCUGCUACGAGGAAUACCAAGGCCGCUCGCCCAAUGCCUACGGCGGGGGCCGCGGCCUCAACAGUUCCAACAACAGUCAUGGCCGGAGCCACCGCUACGGAGGAGGAGGCCGCUACGAGGAGUACCGAGGCCCCUCGCCUGACGCCCACAGUGGGGGCCGCGACAGUUCCAUCAAGAGUUACGGCCUGAGCGACCGCUACGGAGGAGGAGGCCACUACGAGGAGUACCAGGGCAGCUUGCCUGACGCCUACAGCGGCGACCACGACAGAUCCAGCAACAGUUACGGCCGGAGCGACCGCUACUCGAGGGGUCGAGACCGGGUAGGCAGACCGGAUCGUGGGCUCCCUCUGCCCAUGGAAACGGGCAGCCCUCCCCUGCAUGAUUCUUACAGCCGGUCAGGCUGCAGGGUGCCCAGGGGCGGAGGCCGUCAAGGAGGCCGCUUCGAGAGGGGGGAAGGCCGGAGCAGAUACUAAGCAGGAACAGACUUGGGCCCAAAAAUUCCUUUUCAAAGAAACAAAAAGAAGAACCUGUUCUAUGUUAACUACCCAAGGACUAGUAUAAGUAGGAGUUGUUUUUACCUUUUAAGAAUUUCCUGUUAAGAUCUCCAUUUUUAUGCUUUUGUGAGGAAAAACUUAAAAUUAGUUUGAAAUUGUUAAUGUUUCUUUCAACAAGUUCUUGUUAAAAGUAUAAGAUAUG